UUCCACGCUGCCAAUCCUGGGCUCCAGUUUCCCCUUGGGGCCCUGAAGAAAGGGGCUGGGGGUCCCUGGUGCCUGGGACAAAUAGGGAGCUUGGGUGCCCAGGCCUCACCUGGAGGGACCCCAGAGCAUGCAGCAUGGCUCUUCUUUUGCUGCCCUCUUUGCCGACUCUCUCCUCUCCAGACACCCCUGCUCGAGUCCUUGCUACACACGCCCUGGGGUUGUUGCCUCUUGGGGAAGUGCUAGCCUGACUGGUUGUCAAGGGCCCCGUAUUUCUGCCAUGACUCAGUCCCUAAUUUGCUCUUUGAUUCUGGACAAGCCACCUCUCCUUUUUGGGCUCGUGUUUCCAGAGGAGGUAGUGAGUAUCAAAGGUCUCUGUUAGCUCUCGAGUCUGAGAUUUAAAGGCCCCCUAGAACGGAAACCUCAGGGCUAAGGGCUCCUGUCUGUCCUUUUCCAUCCUAUAUCUGCUGUAAAGAACCGUACCUGGCCCAUACAUGCUCAGUAAAUGUUUAUUGAAUGAACCCACUUCUCUAAAUCACAAGCUGCCAGAAGGAGGGGCCUUUCUGAAACUCCAUCUCUAGAGGUUUAUAUUGCUGUCCUCUCAAGAGAUUCCAGAUUCAGACUUUGAGUUCUGUGGCUGUGGGCAAAAGCCAACAAAGACCCAAAUCCUCUGUCCUUGGGAGCUUGAGGAGAGUUUACCGAAACAACAGAAGAAACAAGUGGAACAUCAGCUGGAAGAAGUAACGUGAUUUCGUUUCCUCGCAACAUGACUGCUGGGUUUGGGGGGCACUCAGACAUACAGGCCCCAGUCUCGUCUCACCCACUCCCAGCCUGGGGAUGAAGGCUCACCCUUCAGAUUCCACCCCAUCCCCACAGGGCCCCUGAUAACCUGGUCCCAUGGGUGGGCCUGUCCUGGGGCAUUGGUGGCAUUCUGGGGGCAUGUCUCUUGCUGUGCCAUCUCUGCCUCCCCCUGGUAAGAGCUCUGUCUUCCUCUUCCUACAGGAAAAGAAAGCAAACAACAAGAAACAGAAAGCCAAAAGGGUGCUAGAGGUUCAAAUCCAGACAUUGAACAUACAGAAAGAGGAACUAAAUACGGACCUGUACCACAUGAAACGUUCUCUCAGAUACUUUGAAGAAAAGUCCAAGGAUCUGGCUGUCCGCCUGCAACAUUCAUUGCAGCGUAAAGGAGAGUUAGAGAGUGUUCUCUCUAAUGUCAUGGCCACACAGAAGAAGAAGGCAAACCAGUUGUCCAGCCGCAGCAAAGCACGUACGGAGUGGAAGUUAGAGCAGUCCAUGCGGGAGGAGGCACUACUGAAAGUGCAGCUGACACAGUUCAAGGAGUCAUUUCAACAAGUCCAAUUAGAAAGAGAUGAGUAUUCUGAACAUCUAAAAGGAGAGAGGGCCCGGUGGCAGCAGAGGAUGAGAAAAAUGUCGCAGGAGAUUUGCACAUUAAAGAAAGAGAAGCAGCAAGAUAUGCGUCGGGUAGAGAAGCUGGAGAGGAGCUUGUCCAAACUCAAAAACCAGAUGGCUGAACCCUUGCCCCCGGAGCCCCCAGCAGUGCCCUCUGAGGUGGAGCUGCAGCACCUGAGGAAGGAACUAGAGAGAGUGGCAGGAGAGCUCCAGGCCCAGGUCAAAAACAAUCAGCGCAUAAGUCUCCUGAACCAGCGACAAGAAGAGAGGAUUCGGGAGCAGGAAGAGAGGCUUCGGAAGCAGGAGGAGAGGAUUCAGGAGCAGCACAAGAGCCUUCAGCAGCUGGCCAAGCCACAGAGCGUCUUCAAGGAGCCGAACAAUGAGAACAAGAACGCACUGCAGUUGGAGCAGCAAGUAAAGGAGCUACAGGAGAAGCUUGGCGAGGAGCACCUGGAAGCUGCCAGCCAGCAGAACCAGCAGCUAACGGCCCAGCUGAGCCUCAUGGCUCUCCCUGGGGAAGGACACGGAGGAGAACAUCUGGACAGUGAGGGGGAGGAGGCACCUCGGCCCAUGCCGAGUGUCCCAGAGGACCCGGAGAGCAGGGAGGCCAUGAGCAGCUUUAUGGACCACCUGGAGGAGAAGGCAGACCUGAGUGAGCUGGUGAAGAAAAAAGAACUCUGCUUCAUCCACCACUGGCGAGAGAGAUGCCAUCAGAAAACCCAUCACCUUUUAUCAGAACCAGGGGGCCGUGCCAAAGAUGCGGCACUGGGAGGAGGACACCAUCAGGCUGGAGCUCAGGGAGGAGAUGAAGGUGAAGCUGCUGGAGCUGCAGCAGAUGGUAUUGCGGCUUACAGCAACUACAACAAUGGGCACAGAAAAUUCCUGGCCGCUGCCCACAACUCUGCUGAUGAGCCCGGUCCAGGAGCCCCAGCCCCCCAGGAGCUUGGGGCUGCAGACAAGCAUGGUCAUCUUUGUGAGGUGAGCCUCACCUCCUCUGCCCAAGGAGAGGCCAGGGAGGAUCCUCUCCUUGACAAGCCUACUGCACAGCCGAUCGUGCAGGACCACCAGGAGCACCCAGGCUUGGGCAGCAACUGCUGUGUGCCAUUCUUGUGCUGGGCUUGGCUGCCAAGAAGAAGGAGAUAAACAUCACCAUCCUCAAAGAGCUGCUCAAGAAAUUUUUAAAUAAGAAACCAAGUUAUGGGGUUAAUCUCCUACACAAUUCAUUUACUUCCUUUGAAUGUUAGAGUCACUCAUGAUUAUUUGUUUUUCUAAUUUAUAGUUUUAAGUUUAUUUGUAAAAAGUUAAAAGAGAGUGGGUGUCUGUGGCUCUCACUGAUGUUCACUCUGGCAUCCUUUAGCAUUUUUCUUUUUUAAUUUCAUAAUUGUAGGUCAUUAGCGUGCAUAUCGAGUUUGCCCUUACGUGGUGGGAGUUCAAACACACAAAGACCCACUCUUUGCCCAAAACUGUUCUCUUUGGUUUGGAAUAGGCUGCCAUGCUUUUUUAAUGUUAUUGCAGCAUGUAUAUUCACUACAGAAUUCAGACAAAAUUUGCCUAUGUUCUGCUGUUGUUUGAUCUAAUCUUAAUCACAGUGAGCUCUUCAUUAGCUCAAUAUGUAGUUUGCCCCCAAGUGUGCACUGUUUAUUACUUUGUAAUAUGCCACUAUGAGUACUGACAUUUAGAGUUGUUUAAAGGCCAAGAACUGGAAACAGCCUUUCCUCCAUUUUCUGUGUGUUGGUGAUGGGAGUGAUAACCUUUUGGGGGAGCUUUUUAAAUCUCACAGAAGAGGAAAGUGGCCUCCUCUGGCAGGUACGUGCAGGAUAGAGUGUGUUUCAUCUGUUCCGGUGCCCGGAAUUAGCAGUGUAUUAUGGUGGUUCCCUUAGGAUUUGUAUGUGCUCUGGGCUCAUGAAGAUACUGCAUCAUGAGCUGCAGCAGUUGUACUCUUUUUCGAUGACCUAAAAAGGGCUUAUUUCUGAGGAAUGAAAGGUUCCCAUCAUUGACUGUGGAUGUGGGAAACCUUUCCUAGCUUAGAGCAUUUGUAUCUACAAUACAUUUUAAAGUCAGAGUUCAUGUUACCUGUUUUAAUCACAUGACUACAUGUCCCAGUACACAAAAGGGCACUGGUUGGCAUUCUUCUUAAUGUAUUUAGUGAAGAUCAUAAGAAAUCCUUUAUGAGUUCAAACGUUCCUGGAACAGGCAUACAGGCUCUAGUCAAGAAUGAAUUAGAGUGAAGGAAAGCUGUGUGACACCUGGCAUUCCUCUCUGUUCACGGAGAUUCUUUGAGGCUUGAAGAUUGAUUUUACCAUCUAGACCUCUUUGGCUAAUACCUAUUCUUCAACCACCUUGGUUACUCUGACAUAGGAAUUUACUUCUUUUUCUUUGAAUGGAAAACACUUUAAAAAAUAAUAGAAACAUUAUUAUAAACUAAUAUAUGUGAGAUACUUAGUUGAAACAAAAAGGAGUUUUAGUAGACGGUAUUGUACUCUCUUUGAAAAUCAAGGAGAAGUUUAUGAAACUUAAAAUGUGUACAAACUGCAGUGCAAUCUACUGUUCGUGAAUGUCAAUGUAUUAUCAGGAAACGUGUCUAUACAAUCACAGAGUUAUAUUUUCUCACAGACUUCUUUACAAAGUGAAAUAUGUUUUUGUACCUCUGGGUUUCUGUUCGGGACAUAUUUUGUGCAAUAUUUAUGUGAUUGUGCCUAUGCAUGAUGAAUGAAUACAUUUCAGUUAUAUAUUGCCUAAAUCAUAACUUGAUGAUGCUUGGGAAAGACUCAACAGUUAAAACUUCAUGAAGUUCUAAUGUCUGUGUUCCAAAACACAUCACAUUGUUAGGAUGCAGGGAGAUAGGUGUGUGUGCUCCCUGCGGUGGGGAUUUCUAGUUACUAGAUCAUCUCCAUUUUUAGCAUUUGGCAUCCUCAUGAUACUUCUAUAAAUAUGACAUUAACAGGAGAGCAACAAUACGAUUUUACCGAUGGAAUAACAGAUUUGCUGGCAUUCACUGAAAGAGUGCAAAUAUUCGGUCCUUGUGACUUCCACUGACUCUUCCAAAUUUUAUGAAUGUAUCAAUGUAUUAGAUAAACCCAGUUUCAGAAUGAUAAAGAAAAAAUUUAGACCAAAUAAUGCAGCUAAUUAACAGUGGUACGAUUUGUAGCCCGUGGGUUUAAAAUGCACUUAAAGUCCUGUUCUCGCCUUUUAUUUUCUGAACUUGCCGCUUUUGCAUUCUUUGAGUUCAGUUUAAAGACAGUUACUUUAAGAGCAUUUUAAACCCUCGGGCUAGAAAUCGGACCACUGUUAAUCAGCCACAUUAUUUGGUCUAACGUUUUUUCUUUUAUCAUUCUGAAACUGGGUUUAUCUAAUACAUUGAUAAAUUAUUGCAAAGGUACUUUUAUCGUUGAAAUCACUUCACUUUUACCCUGAUAAAUAUCAGUGACUAGGAAUGACCUUCGGAUAGCGUUUAGCAUCUGUAACCAAUCUGACAAUAAUGUGUUCAUGAGGUGCCUAUGGAUUAAAUCACACACUGGCAUAUUUAAGCUGAAGGUCAGUCUGGAAAAUAAAUUUACUAUAUUGACUGAAAUACCACUCUUUGUGUAGGUAUUUGUCAUAUAUUUAAGAAAAAGUUAAAAAGAAUGGAAAUUGUAUGACAAUAACUCAAGUCUUUCUCCAAAGUGCAUGCAGUCUUUUGCGAUACCUCAUUCAGCCGAGUAUUUGUGCUCUUCCUCAUUCAGUAUAAGGCAGCUUUCAGUUUGCUUAGAAGGCAACAUUGGAAUGUUAGAGUUCAUCAGAAACAUAGAAUUUUAAACUGUGAGUUCCACUGAAUACAUUUUAAUGUCUGUAGGAAGAAUCAAAACACCUAUUUAAAGAUGGCAAUAUAUAAUAAUCAUUUUAAAAGUAUUUGAUUCAACCUGAUAAUUUUCCAGAAAUGAAAAAAAAAAAUCAGCUCUAAAACCAAAGCUGAUUUUAGAAAAUUUGAAAAUGUAAAUCAGCCCUAUCCAUAAUAUAGUUUCUCUAAAACUUUAUUUUAAAGAGUCAUUUUAAAAUAAUAUAACUAUUAAAAAAUGUAACUGCUAUCUUAAUGUUCUGAAAUAAUUUAAAACAUUUUAAAAUAUGAAUACUGUAGUAUAAAAGAAAGAAAUGGUGGGAACGAAAAGCAGAGAAAGAAAUGCCAAUUCCAGUCCAAAGUUUUAUUUGCCAAGUUUUCUUAGAAUGAAUUUUACCAGUUUAUGAAUUAUUGUAAAGAGAAUGUGUCGUGGAAAUACUGAAAGAUUUUUCCCUAGAGUGGCCUUAUUGACUGCUGGUGUGAUGCCACUGUAAUGUAAUAAAUUAUUAAGUUGUUUCAA